AGUGCAGCCUAGAGACGCUGACAAAGGAGCGGAGGAGCAGUCGCAGCUGCUUUCCGAGGAAGCCGGUGUUGCCGAGCUGAAGUAGCAGAUCUGCCCCAGUAGAAUCUGAGAGAUCUCACGUCGGGGAACGAGAGGACAAAUGCUAAGUGAAAAUUGACCUUUGAGGGAGAUAAGAAGAGGACUCAAACGUGAAAAAUUGUGUCCUUUGGAUCUUGCCUAAAAAGCAGUCCUGUUCUUUCAGAGUGCAUUGCAUUCUUAAUGUGAAUUCCAGACAGAAAGGAGAAAGUCUACUUUUUCAGAUUGCCAAAAUGCUUUGGAGUUUUUAACUGAAUCUAAGAAAAGUCCAAAAUAGAUUUGAGACUGUAAAAACAGAAACUGCAGCAAGGGGGAUUCAGUGCCAAUGCAUCAACAAAAAAGACAACCAGAGUUAGUGGAAGGAAAUCUUCCUGUUUUCGUGUUCCCCACGGAGCUCAUAUUUUAUGCAGAUGAUCAGUCAACACAUAAGCAAGUGUUGACACUGUACAAUCCCUAUGAGUUUGCCUUAAAGUUCAAAGUUUUGUGUACUACUCCAAAUAAGUAUGUUGUCGUUGAUGCUGCAGGUGCAGUAAAGCCUCAGUGUUGUGUGGAUAUUGUGAUUCGUCAUCGAGAUGUUCGAUCCUGUCACUAUGGUGUAAUAGACAAAUUCCGUCUCCAAGUUUCCGAGCAAAGCCAAAGGAAGGCUUUGGGAAGAAAAGAGGUUGUUGCUACUCUUCUCCCAUCAGCAAAAGAACAACAAAAGGAAGAAGAGGAAAAAAGAUUAAAGGAACAUUUAACUGAAAGUUUAUUUUUUGAGCAGUCGUUUCAACCAGAAAACAGAGCUGUAUCCUCAGGACCUAGUUUACUAACUGUCUUCCUGGGAGUGGUGUGCAUUGCAGCCCUGAUGCUGCCUACACUGGGGGAUGUGGAAUCGCUGGUGCCUCUCUACCUCCACUUAAGUGUGAAUCAAAAAUUAGUGGCUGCUUAUAUCUUAGGUCUUAUCACAAUGGCCAUACUUAGAACAUGAGCAAGGAUUUCAAUUGACUUCUGAAGUAAAUCUGUCUUGAAAAUAUGAAUGUGGACUGCCUUUUAUCUCUAUUUCACUCCAUUAACAUGCAACAAACUAUUGAAUGAUUUCAAAUAAUUGCAAAUGUAUAAUAUAUAUUUUAAAUUAUAAUUUAAUUUGAAGGACUGCAGAACAUUAUUUUACAGACAGCAAGGAUGCUUCUGAGUGACACCUAGGAAAUUAUUUGAAGAAAUUCUUUUUAUAUCUAUACCUGUUGUGUAAGAAACUUUAAAACAUUUGUUAUUUUCUCACCUUUUUUUCUAAUUCACUUUGAUUGCUAGGGGUCAUGUAUGCUUCGAAGUUACAGGACUAAAAGAGCAAACUGACCGGCCUAAAACUAAAAUGACAUUUAUUCCCUAGCUACAAACAUCAGCGUUAUUAUGUUAAUUAUACCUUGCCCUCUAUCAUUAUAAAUGGUUGCCAUGGUGUUUCUAAAAAUAAGUGUUUUACCAUUAAUGUGUAGAGGGCAAACAAAGCAUAAAGUACUAAGGGAUCAUGCUUAUCCUAGGGUCUCACAGAAGAGAGGACAUAUUUAAUUAAUCUUGUGAAUUACAGAACAGGUUGUGGUCCAGACACCAAGAAUCAUAGGGGUUUUUUUUUAAAAAACCUAAUAGAAGUAGGGUGACCUCUCUCUUUGGUCUAAGAGUUCUAAAGGAAGGUAGGCAUCUGUUUAAUUAGUUGGUUCACCCUGGCUUUACCUCUGGUUAAUGCUUUGUGUUAAUAGGAAGGAAAAAUCACUUUAUCUUUUCUUCCAAGCCCCUCCCUGCCUGACUUACCCAGACUGGGAUUACCAGAUACCAGGUGAUUUAUGUGGAGAUGAUUUUUCACCUUUAAACUCUAAGCCAAGUGUAAGAAACUCUUGAUAGCUAUGUCUAUUUUAUAUCAGUCACUGAGACUUUUUUUUAAGUUUUUAUUUAUUAUUAAGACAACUUUGCCAAAAAAGUCCCCUAAGCACAACUAUUUACAUUUCUUUAUAGCCUCUUCUGAUCUCUAACACAUAUGCAGUUUUAACUGUUAUUUUCAUAGUAACUGAUCUUUUGUCUAAGGAUUUUUACCUGAAAGCACAAUGUAUUGAGUCUCUUGAAAAUCAUCUUUCAGAUCUUUUUACAGAAUGAACUUAUGCACUGCUACUGUAGUAUUCUCAAGGAAUAUAUGUAAACACAAAUGUAUGCCUGAGGUUGGUUUUUGCAGAAAACAGUCUCUGCUUCUAAAAACUUCUAUGUCUAGUCUUCCAUAGGAAAUCCUCACUGUUUAACCAUGUGAGGAGCCUAAGUCAUUAAACGGAUCAUGUCUGUACAUUGUGUAAUGAAUGAAAAGCACAUAAAUGUAAUCUACUUUGAACUUUGUAAAAAUGAUGUGUGGAGGCUAUUCUUGUUUCUCCAUCUCAAGUCCUGUGUGUGCACGUGUGUGCAAGUGCACAUGUGUGUGUGUAAUAACACAUUGUAAAGAACAGAAAUUACUUUAAAAAAUAAACAGAAAUGGAGACCUGA